GGCGUGCGGCGCCGUUGCGGGCGGGAGCGGCUGCAACGCCGGUGCCUGAGGAGCGAUGCCGAGGGAAAUCAUCACCCUACAGUUGGGCCAGUGCGGCAAUCAGAUUGGGUUCGAGUUCUGGAAACAGCUGUGCGCCGAGCAUGGUAUCAGCCCCGAGGGCAUCGUGGAGGAGUUCGCCACCGAGGGCACUGACCGCAAGGACGUCUUUUUCUACCAGGCAGACGAUGAGCACUACAUCCCCCGGGCCGUGCUGCUGGACUUGGAACCCCGGGUGAUCCACUCCAUCCUCAACUCCCCCUAUGCCAAGCUCUACAACCCAGAGAACAUCUACCUGUCGGAACAUGGAGGAGGAGCUGGCAACAACUGGGCCAGCGGAUUCUCCCAGGGAGAAAAGAUCCAUGAGGACAUUUUUGACAUCAUAGACCGGGAGGCAGAUGGUAGUGACAGUCUAGAGGGCUUUGUGCUGUGUCACUCCAUUGCUGGGGGGACAGGCUCUGGACUGGGUUCCUACCUCUUAGAACGGCUGAAUGACAGGUAUCCUAAGAAGCUGGUGCAGACAUACUCAGUGUUUCCCAACCAGGACGAGAUGAGCGAUGUGGUGGUCCAGCCUUACAAUUCACUCCUCACACUCAAGAGGCUGACGCAGAAUGCAGACUGUGUGGUGGUGCUGGACAACACAGCCCUGAACCGGAUUGCCACAGACCGCCUGCACAUCCAGAACCCAUCCUUCUCCCAGAUCAACCAGCUGGUGUCUACCAUCAUGUCAGCCAGCACCACCACCCUGCGCUACCCUGGCUACAUGAACAAUGACCUCAUCGGCCUCAUCGCCUCGCUCAUUCCCACCCCACGGCUCCACUUCCUCAUGACCGGCUACACCCCUCUCACUACGGACCAGUCAGUGGCCAGCGUGAGGAAGACCACGGUCCUGGAUGUCAUGAGGCGGCUGCUGCAGCCCAAGAACGUGAUGGUGUCCACAGGCCGAGACCGCCAGACCAACCACUGCUACAUCGCCAUCCUCAACAUCAUCCAGGGAGAGGUGGACCCCACCCAGGUCCACAAGAGCUUGCAGAGGAUCCGGGAACGCAAGUUGGCCAACUUCAUCCCGUGGGGCCCCGCCAGCAUCCAGGUGGCCCUGUCGAGGAAGUCUCCCUACCUGCCCUCGGCCCACCGGGUCAGCGGGCUCAUGAUGGCCAACCACACCAGCAUCUCCUCGCUCUUCGAGAGAACCUGUCGCCAGUAUGACAAGCUGCGUAAGCGGGAGGCCUUCCUGGAGCAGUUCCGCAAGGAGGACAUGUUCAAGGACAACUUUGAUGAGAUGGACACAUCCAGGGAGAUUGUGCAGCAGCUCAUCGAUGAGUACCAUGCGGCCACACGGCCAGACUACAUCUCCUGGGGCACCCAGGAGCAGUGAGUCCCCCAGGACAGGGACCCUCAUCUGCCUUACUGGUUGGCCCAAGCCCUGCCUGACUGACCACCCCCUCAGAGCACAGAUCAGGGACCUCACGCAUCUCUUUCUCAUAUACAUGGACUCUCUGUUGGCCUGCAAACACAUUUACUUCUCCUCUUAUGAGACUAUUUAUCUUUAAUAAAGCACUGGAUAUAAAUCAA